GCGGCUGGACCCUGGCCUGCGCUGGCUGGGGAGGAAGCGGUUCUAGGGGAGCGUGCGGGCGCCGGGGUCCGGCGGCGAGAGGCCACCUUCUGGCCUUGCGAUGAAUCCUCGGUUUCCCCUUCUCAGAUGGGGUUUUCGUGAGGGUACAACGUCGGCAUUAGACAUUCCAGGUGACGCCCGUACGCGGUGGGCGGUUCGGGCCGGAGCUCUGGAACGCUGGCCCUGGAGGCGUCGACCCCUCGUUACUGAUGCAGGGACGCGGUGCGGACCAGUCAGGCCCAGAGCUCGUCCUUAGAUGUGGGUUCGAAUCUCUGCCCCGCCAACUUGUGAUCGUAUCGACUCGGCCCAGACGCAAUUUUCUUCUCUGCAAAAUCGUCAUAAGAAUAAUCACUUGUCAGGGUAGCUGCGGGCAUCCCAUUCGUUCCUUUCAUCAGCGCCGGGCAUAUGGGGCGUCAGAGGCUGAGAACGUUGCCGUGAAGAGGCUUAAAAGCAAGACCCGGAGUGGCGACCUUAAAGAGGACGGACUGAAGAAACGCGGGAAUGAGCUCCAGACGCGGGAGUUUCCUCUCUACAAAGUUACACUGCAGCAGCUGUCUACCCUGCCCCUUGUCUUUUGAGAAGUUCAAACCUUCAGAAAAGUUGCAAGAACACGAAAAUUUUGCCAAAGACCUUGAAAUGUUUGCAAGACAUGCGAAAAGAACCACAAUUAACACUGAAGAUGUGAAGCUCUUAGCCAGGAGGAGUAAUUCACUGCAUAUGCAGGAAGCGGCAGGAAUAAGGAAAAGCAGCCUCCUGACUUUCCUCGCUUGGUGGUUUGAGUGGACCUCCCAGGCCAGUGCCGGGCCCCUCAUAGGAGAGGAAGCCCGGGAGGUGGCCAGGCGGCAGGAAGGCGCACCCCCCCAGCAAUCUGCGCGCCGGGACAGAAUGCCCUGCAGGAACUUCUUCUGGAAGACCUUCUCCUCCUGCAAAUAAAACCUCACCCAUGAAUGCUCACGCAAGUGUAAUGACAGACCUGAAUAAAAUGUAUUAAGCAGCAGUGAUCUUUCCUCUCCUCCUUCCCAAGUCAUUUGAAAAGUGUUUGUUAUUUAAAUUCCAAUAAUGCCCAAUACUGACGUGUCUUGAGUAAUUUGGAACCCAAAGUGAAGAUCUUUGAUAAAGAUUUUUUUGUGGUUCGACUGGACUGUGCUGAGUGCGGGCACUGGGCUUUUCUUCUGAUGUUCAUUAUGGUGCUGGGAAGCUCUGUCUUUGAUUUAAAAUAAAAUAGCUAAAGGCUACACAAUUAAGAGUUCAGAAUAACAUCUUAUUUCAGUUUAUGAAUUGAUAUGAAUUGUCUAAUUUAAAAAAUAUUUCCCUCACAUUAAAAGCAAAUUUUUAAUAUCAGGCUCGAAGAGCAAAAUGAUUAUUCCUCAUGUUUUAGCUGAAAUUAAUUUUAAAACAUAUUAAACAGAAAACCUGCUGACAUGCCUGUGAAACUGAUACUCGAACUUGCUGUUAUGUACCAGUUUUAAUUAGUAGCUUAAUGGGUUGCAA